CUUCCCCUCUCCCUGUGCAACCAGGCUGUCAACACCAGACUCUAGGCCUCUGCCAGUGAUCUAUGGACCUCAGGGCCCCCGAGCUUCAGCCUGCUCAGGUAGGGCCAUGAGUGUGAUAGGGCGAGGUGUGACUGAGCAUGAGAGUGACAGUGAGCAUGUGAGAGCAGGAGGGGGUGACAGUGUGAGUGCGUGUGUGAGUGUGGCUGUGAACGUGCAUGAGGAUGUGUGCAGGUGAGCAUCUACAUGAGUGCAGGUGUGAGUGUGCCACAUUGUGUGUGAAUGAGUGUGUGAGUGUAUCUGGAGCCUGGGCUCUCCUUAGCUGCGGGGGAGCCGGGCUCAGGGAGGAGCUCCCUCUGGCUCAAGAGAAUACAGUGAUCUGAGAGCCAAAUUCCAGCCUGGAGUGGGAGGGGGUCAGCUCACCUUUGCUUCUACAGUCCCUUAAGGGCUGGUUGGAGUGGGGAAAAAGCAGAGAAGCAGCAGUUUAGGAAAAAAGGUAUGUAGUGGUUGGAUCAUGAAGAGGACUUGGAGUCUGUGGCCCUGUGGGGGCUCAGAACACUGUCAGAUUAUUUCGGUAUGUGUCAUUUCCCGGCAAGCUGAGACCCUCAGAAGAGAAGCAGUUGCCUCCCCUUGGUCCCUUUCCUCCUCCUGGGCCUAGGAGAGCUGCGAGCCCCUGUGGGCAAGAGGUGAGGACUGUUCUCUUGGAUCUGUGGCCAGGUGGAAGCUCUCCAAAGUCUUGGGGGAUGGGGAGGGUAUGGAGGCUCACCAGCACCUUGCUGGAGGGCCCUCACCCAUAGGCAGGAAGGACAGAGCAGACGUCUCUCUGGUACCCACUCCUACCAACGCACUGACCCUGGAGGGUUACUGCUUCGUGUGGGGUAAGAUGGAGAACCUGGGAGGUUGGAAGCUGGUGAGAUUUAGGAACUGGGAGCCUGCAGUGUGUGGAGGUUGUGGGGGUGGAAUGUGUGUUUGGUGUGAGUGCUGGGGUCUGCGUGUUGGUGUGAGGAGGUGAGAGGCUGUCUGAGUUUGCCUUUGUAUCUGUAAGAUUGUAUGUUUCAAUCCCUGUAGGUGUGACUGUUUAUGUCUUUUUGUGAGUGAGGACCUGUCUGUGUGAUCACAUGAGUGUGUACGAUCUGUAUUUGAGAGUGCAUGUGUGUGGAAGCAUGCUAAUUGUGUGGGAGAGGUGAAAGAUGAUUGACAGGGAAGGGGCGGAGGGUGGGAGCCCACACUGAGUGCACAGUUUCAUCCUUCCUCAGGCUCUGCUUGUCAUGGCUGAAAUCCCCUGGACUGCAUUGGGACCAUACUGCUGAGAGUCUGGUUGCUGGGCUUCAGCUGACAGAACAUCAGAGCCCCAGGAUGGGAUAGCCACAAGUUGGGAAGGUGAGGCAGGGUGAGGGGCUUGAUGAUGGGGAGCAGGCAGAAAGAACAGGCUGCAGAGCUAGGGCUGCUGGAGCCUGAUGUCUGGUCCAAGUUCCAGCUCCUCCACUCAUGGGGUGAGCUGGGGCAAGUCACUUCACUCUCUGAGCCUCAGUUUCCUCAUCAGAACAAUGGGCCUGUACACUAAGCAUUAUCCACCCCAAAUCCUAGAAGCCUGCCUUCUCCUCCUGGCUCUGGGAAGUUGACCAUUGGAGGCCUGGGACACUGGCCUGUCUGGAGGCUGGGGAAGUAUGAGACGACCCCUUCUUCCCUUCCCUGCGCCCAGAAGGCCUGACUUGUCCUACUGCACCCCUCCCAUCACAGUGAUCUGUGUGGGCUCAUAACAACAUAAGCUAGACGGUGAUCCUGUAUCACCUUCCUGCAUUCUGGGAGGCUCGGCCUCCAACUCCCAGACCAGGGAAUGGUCUCCACUCCUCCAAUCCUUCCCAGGUUCAGAAGCAGGAAUGGGGGAAGUCCUGCCUGUCCCCUCUCUGACUUUACUUUCCCUUUCUAGAGCAGGGGUAUUCUGGGAUGGGAGGACUGAGUGUCCCUGCUGCCUGGUCCUCAGAGUUGGCUAGCUCCCCCCAUGCCCCUCAUUCCCCCGCCUGCUCGCCUGUAGAGCUGUGGCCCGGGCAGCUGUCCGGCUGAGUGGGUUAGCAACACAAGACAGAUGGCGAGGGAUUAUCUCAGCUUCUCAGAGCACGAUGGUGGCAGCGGCGGGGGUGGGGGGAAGGCUCUCACACCCUCCCCAUGUGUGUGUACACACACACACACAAAUGCACACAUGCAGCUCCCCGCUCCUGCCCCAGACCCAGCCCAGCCUCCUGCUAUUUAUGAGGCGGGCAGGAAGACAAGAGGAGAGAUGAGAUUAUGAGAAUUGGUGAGAACCGUGGGACUUGGCAAUCUUGUCCCUGCCCCACUUGGCUCCCAGACCACAGGCUGAACCAGCUUCUCAGGCCCUUCUUGGACCCUGCCCCUGCUAUUGUGAUUUCUCUGCAGCUGCCACCACUGGGAAUGGUACAUUCAGGAGGGCAUGGUUUUACAGAGAAGUUUGAGGCCCAGAGAUGUGCGAGCUGCACUCAAAGUCACACAGCAAGUUUGGUUCAUUAGCAGGGUCUAGAGGAGUCCCAGGAGCAGCCAGGACAGGCGGAAGCAGUGGCUGCCAUGGAGGAGGACAAGCUCUUAUCUGCAGUGCCUGAGGAAGGCGAUGCCACCCGUGACCCCGGUCCAGAGCCUGAAGAGGAGCCAGGGGUCCGGAAUGGGAUGGCCAGUGAGGGCCUGAACAGCAGCCUCUGCAGCCCAGGGCACGAGCGAAGGGGCACCCCAGCGGACACUGAGGAACCCACGAAGGACCCAGAUGUGGCCUUCCAUGGCCUCAGCCUUGGCCUCUCUCUCACCAAUGGCCUAGCCCUGGGGCCAGACUUGAACAUUCUGGAAGAUUCAGCGGAGUCCAGGCCCUGGAGGGCUGGCGUGCUGGCAGAGGGGGACAAUGCUUCCAGGAGCCUCUACCCAGAUGCUGAGGACCCUCAGCUGGGGUUGGAUGGUCCCGGGGAGCCAGAUGUGCGGGAUGGCUUCAGCGCCACGUUUGAGAAGAUUCUGGAGUCAGAGCUGCUGCGGGGCACCCAGUACAGCAGCCUCGACUCCCUAGACGGGCUGAGCCUCACGGAUGAGAGCGACAGCUGCGUCAGCUUCGAGGCCCCCCUCACACCCCUCAUCCAGCAGCGGGCCCGUGACAGCCCUGAGCCAGGGGCUGGGUUGGGCAUUGGGGACAUGGCGUUUGAGGGGGACAUGGGGGCAGCUGGUGGUGAUGGGGAGCUGGGCAGCCCCCUGCGGCGCUCCAUCUCCAGCAGCCGCUCUGAGAAUGUCCUGAGCCGCCUGUCUCUCAUGGCCAUGCCCAAUGGAUUCCAUGAAGAUGGCCCUCAGGGCCCAGGGGGGGAUGAGGAUGAUGAUGAGGAGGACACGGACAAGUUGCUGAACUCAGCCAGUGACCCCAGCCUGAAGGAUGGCCUGUCAGACUCAGACUCUGAGCUCAGCAGCUCGGAGGGGUUGGAGCCUGGUAGUGCAGACCCUCUGGCCAACGGGUGCCAGGGGGUCAGUGAAGCUGCUCAUCGGCUGGCACGCCGUCUCUACCACCUCGAGGGCUUCCAGCGCUGUGAUGUGGCCCGGCAGCUGGGCAAGAACAACGAGUUUAGCAGGCUGGUGGCCGGGGAGUACCUCAGUUUCUUCGACUUCUCGGGCUUGACUCUGGACGGAGCACUCAGAACAUUCUUGAAGGCCUUCCCGCUGAUGGGGGAGACACAAGAGCGUGAGCGGGUCCUCACACACUUCUCCCGCCGGUACUGCCAGUGCAACCCUGAUGACAGCACUUCGGAAGAUGGGAUCCACACGCUCACCUGUGCCCUGAUGCUGCUCAACACGGACCUGCACGGCCACAACAUUGGCAAAAAGAUGUCCUGUCAGCAAUUCAUUGCCAACUUGGACCAGCUGAAUGAUGGCCAAGACUUUGCCAAAGACCUGCUGAAGACCCUUUACAACUCCAUCAAGAAUGAAAAGCUGGAAUGGGCCAUUGAUGAGGAUGAGCUGAGGAAAUCCCUGUCUGAGCUGGUGGAUGACAAGUUCGGGACAGGCACGAAGAAGGUGACGCGAAUCCUGGAUGGUGGCAACCCCUUCCUGGAUGUCCCACAGGCGCUCAGUGCCACCACCUACAAGCACGGCGUCCUGACCCGGAAGACUCACGCUGACAUGGAUGGCAAGAGGACGCCCCGUGGGAGGCGUGGCUGGAAGAAAUUCUACGCAGUGCUCAAAGGGACCAUCCUGUACCUGCAGAAGGAUGAGUACAGGCCUGACAAAGCUCUAUCGGAGGGUGACCUGAAGAACGCCAUUCGCGUGCAUCACGCUCUGGCCACCAGGGCCUCUGACUACAGCAAGAAGUCCAACGUGCUGAAGCUUAAGACAGCCGACUGGAGGGUAUUCCUCUUCCAGGCACCGAGCAAGGAAGAAAUGCUGUCCUGGAUCCUCAGGAUCAACCUGGUGGCAGCCAUCUUCUCUGCCCCGGCCUUCCCAGCCGCUGUCAGCUCCAUGAAGAAGUUCUGUCGGCCCCUGCUGCCCUCCUGCACCACCCGCCUCUGCCAGGAGGAGCAACUGCGGUCUCAUGAGAAUAAGUUGAGGCAGCUGACUGCGGAGCUGGCCGAACACAGGUGUCACCCAGUCGAGAGGGGCAUCAAGUCCAAGGAGGCCGAGGAGUACCGGUUGAAGGAGCACUAUCUCACCUUCGAGAAAAGCCGUUAUGAGACCUAUAUCCACCUCCUGGCUAUGAAAAUCAAAGUGGGCUCAGAUGAUCUGGAGCGGAUUGAGGCCCGGCUGGCCACUCUGGAAGGGGAUGACCCUUCUCUCCGGAAGACACAUUCAAGCCCUGCCCUCAGCCAGGGCCAUGUGACUGGCAGCAAAACCACAAAGGAUGCCACUGGGCCUGAUACUUAGCUGACAUGGAUUUGCAGACCCCAGGGUGGGCAGAUGUCUCCAGUGGGGUCAGUGAGCACAAUUCCAGCCAGGGGCCACUUGGACCAAGCUCCAGUCAGUUGAUGGGCAGCUAGAGGGGUGCAGAAAGCCUGUGGGCCCAGGAGAUGGAGAUGCCGUUUGUGGCGUUGAUCUCCUUGCGUCCUUGGGCAUCUCCGGGCAUCAGACCCUCUCCCUGGCCCUUGUUUUCCUCUCCACCAUGGAGCCUCAUUUUGUAGGCCAGUUGUGUGCAUGCUCUAGACACCACCUCGCUGGAGAAGCUGGAAGGGCUGUUGUCUUCCCAGGUCUUUCUCUUCUCAUCAAGCUCCUCUCCUCAUCUUUUUUGUGUGUGAGGGCAGGUCUUGACUCUAGGUCUCAGCUGGAACCCCACCCUUUCUCCUCCUCCUUCCUCUGAGUUGACCAGCAGCAGGUCUGCCGACCACCAGCACCAUCCUCUCCUCCCAGCAGCCUCCAGAACCAUGCCCAGGUCUCCUGCCUCACAUCACAAUAAUCUGGGACCCAGGCUUGUGCCCUUUCAGUGUAAAGCUGACUCCAUCACAUGUGCAUCCACUUCUUUUCAUCCAUUGAGAUCACACUGCCUCCUUUUUAUACAGACACAAAUAUACAUCUAUAAGAAUAAUAUAUACAUAAGGAACCCCUGAAAGAUGGUUUUGGAACUGGAAUCAGUUAGAGGAUGAAAUCAGAUAAAGGAAAAGCCUAUUUUGGAGCUUCCCCUGUUAGGAAGGAUGGCUGCACCUGGCCCCCUGGCAUUCCUGACGCUCUAGGAGGGAAGGGGGAGGCAGUGCUGGCCUCCCUUGCCCUGUUUUUCCCUCUUCCAGCUGACCUGUGACUUAUACUGCUCUUACCGAUGAUACUUUUGGAAAAAAUAGAGCGUGUAUGCACCGCCCCGUUUGUCCCAUGGAUAUCCUGGGGUGUGAGUCGGAUGGGACCACGGCCCUGUUUAUAUUUGGGUCUUUAUGUUGGUGCUGCCAGGUCUCUGAGCUCCAGAGGUGGCCUCUUGGACAGAUCUACUGCUAUAGGAAUAAAAGACACUCUGUCUCGCAAAUGGCUGCUUGUCAACAAGCCCAAAGAUGCUUGUCGGAGGACGGUUAUGGAAGCCCUUAAUUCUUGGUUGUGGGAAAAGGUGGAAUGACAAGUUAUUGAUUGUUUUUCUGUCGCUAUUUCUUUCAUUUGUCUAGUGAAUCAGAAAGGCUUAGCCAAGGCCACAUCUGGGAAGAGUGGAGAAAUUUGCCACUUGACGAUCACGGAUUAGCUAGCACCUUUAAGCCCUGCAUUUCUCCAACUGACAAGUGGGUGGGGGUGAUGGCACAUUCAGUGUGGCUAUGAAGAGCGAAUCCUCUCUAUUGUUUAAAUAGAUUACUGUAGUUUGGCCAGGAAUUUGGCGUCAGUGGUAACACACUUAGUUAAUAAAAUAAGCCAGGCUUGCAACUAAGUAUCUAACUUUACAGGCCCACUCACAUUUGAGGCAAGGGGCUAUUGAGUAUGUGGAGAGAUGUAGUGAUUUAAAUUCAGAUUAUUUAAGUUGGAUCAGCUGAAGUGUGUUUUAGACCCAAACCAUCUGGCCCCUUCGUUUUGCUCAGAGGAAGUAAAUGUUCACUUAAAUGAAAUUGAAAACGCCAUGUGGCACCACAAAAGAGCUCUCUGUACUUUCCCCAUGCUGCCUCAAAAGUUCUGUGAGUUUCGGGGUCAGUGUCCCACCCUUCACUUCCCGAGGGCGGGUGAGUGGAGAGCAGAGCCAGGAGCUCUGGCAGCUGUGGACAGAUGUGCUUCCUGAGCAUGGGUUGUGCCUCCCAUCAGUAAAAAAAUGUUUAGUUCACUUCCUUAAUUGUAUAAUUAUUUAUUUGUAAAUUAUAUACAUGUACUACUGUACUAAAAUAUUAUGUACAUUAUAAAACAUACACAAAAAUAGAAAUUUAAAAAAGAUGAGAUGAAAAUAAAUCUAAGUCAAAGUUCUAA